GUCAGUGCGGCGGGGCGCGCGAGCGGCGCCAGCUCGGGGCAGCGGAACCCAGAGAAGCUGAGGGGGCGGUAGCGGCGGCGACGGCGACGACGACGACUCCCGCGCGUGUGCCCAGCCUCUUCCCGCCGCAGCCGCCCUUUUCCUCCCUCCCUUACGUCCCCGAGUGCGGCAGUACCGCCUCCUUCCCAGCCGCGCGGCUUCCUCCAGACCUCUCGGCGCGGGUGAGCCCUAUUCCCAGAGGCAGGUGGUGCUGACCCUGUAACCCAAAGGAGGAAACAGCUGGCUAAGCUCAUCAUUGUUACUGGUUCCCAGAGAGGGGGCUUCUUGAAAAGCAAGUAGAGCAGAAGACUGGUGAGCACGGUGUUUCCCAGCAUCUCCACAGUGCCAGCACAGAGGAGGACACUCAAGAAAUGUUUGUUAAGUGGGCACCAUGUCCUUGAAGCUUCAGGCAAGCAAUGUAACCAACAAGAAUGACCCCAAGUCCAUCAACUCUCGAGUCUUCAUUGGAAACCUCAACACAGCUCUGGUGAAGAAAUCAGAUGUGGAGACCAUCUUCUCUAAGUAUGGCCGUGUGGCCGGCUGUUCUGUGCACAAGGGCUAUGCCUUUGUUCAGUACUCCAAUGAGCGCCAUGCCCGGGCAGCUGUGCUGGGAGAGAAUGGGCGGGUGCUGGCCGGGCAGACCCUGGACAUCAACAUGGCUGGAGAGCCUAAGCCUGACAGACCCAAGGGGCUAAAGAGAGCAGCAUCUGCCAUAUACAGUGGCUACAUCUUUGACUAUGAUUACUACCGGGACGACUUCUACGACAGGCUCUUCGACUACCGGGGCCGUCUGUCGCCCGUGCCAGUGCCCAGGGCGGUCCCUGUGAAGCGACCCCGGGUCACAGUCCCUUUGGUCCGGCGUGUCAAAACUAACGUACCUGUCAAGCUCUUUGCCCGCUCCACAGCUGUCACCACCAGCUCAGCCAAGAUCAAGUUAAAGAGCAGUGAGCUGCAGGCCAUCAAGACGGAGCUGACACAGAUCAAGUCCAAUAUCGAUGCCCUGCUGAGCCGCUUGGAGCAGAUCGCUGCGGAGCAAAAGGCCAAUCCAGAUGGCAAGAAGAAGGGUGAUGGAGGUGGCGCCGGCGGCGGCGGCGGUGGUGGUGGCAGCGGUGGCGGUGGCAGUGGUGGUGGCGGUGGCGGUGGCAGCAGCCGGCCACCAGCCCCCCAAGAGAACACAACUUCUGAGGCAGGCCUGCCCCAGGGGGAAGCACGGACCCGAGACGACGGCGAUGAGGAAGGGCUCCUGACACACAGCGAGGAAGAGCUGGAACACAGCCAGGACACAGACGCGGAUGAUGGGGCCUUGCAGUAAGCAGCCUGACAGGAGCAAUGGCCACCAGCAGGUGAAGGGCAUCGCUGCCCCAGGCCUCAAGCCGGGCACCCAACCCUGGAUGCCACCCCCCAGCGGGUACCAGAGGAAAGCUGGCAGCAGGCGCCUCCUCCCCCAACGCAUCCCAGCCAGUGCCAUGUCCUCUGCAGGUGGAGUUACUGGCCUACUCCUUCCCCAUGAGCCCUCCCUGUCUGCACUGCCCAGGCCAGAGGGUAGAGCACAGGGGUUUCCCCAUACUACCUCCCCUCCCCAGGACACUCCCAGGCUUGGGUUUUUUCUAUAGGUUUGGCGGGGGGCCACAGGGAGGGGACCCUGACAAUAAAGAGAUUGGAUCCCAACCUGUUCUGAGAUGGGAUGGUUUGUGUUUUCUCAUGAAGAUAUCCCGGCCCCUCUGCCAACCAAAAAGCUGGUCUAGGGUGCCUAAUACUGAUCCAUCUGGACCUUAGUGUCCUCAGUGGUGAUUAAAAUGGCCAGUGGGGCCACUGGGGAGGGUUGGAUAUGCUGGCCCAUGAGCAUCUUGCUGGCUGAAGUGUCAAGCAGUUGUGACCCACUUGGUUUACCCCAUAGUAGGUCAAGACCUUAUCUCUUUCCCCAGCUUCUAAGUCUGGUCUUUCCCAGCUCUUAAAAGGAUUCUAGAGUCUGCCAGUCUCUACCUUCUCUCUUCUGGCUUAGGACACUAUAAUUUUUUCAUUUGGACGUUGUCCUCCCACCAGCCUCCCAGUCUUCUGCCUCUGCCCUGUACCAUCUCCCAGCAGCCACGCAGUCUUUCUGAAACGUAUCCCUUCCCUGCCUAAAAUCCCUUUACUGACUCUUCAUCAUCAGGACAAAACCCUACCUCCUGAAUGUAGGGUGUAAGAUCCUGCUUACUCCAGCCUCUCCUGUUUCUUGUCACCACCCCUUUCCUGCCCCUGACACAAACCCUACAUCUCAGUCUCACAAAACACACAAGUUCUUCACACUCCGGGCAGGUUUGGUAGCAAGGAAUAGAGCGUACUCCAGUGACAGCAAUCAGUAGGAAGUUUGCAUCCGGAGACACGCAGCCUGUCUGCCCCUGUCUUGGGCCACCCGUCUAGACAUUUGUUCUCUAACAAUCAGCCGGGUUCCUUCAAACGUGUGCUGCUUAUACAUGCUCAUUGUGUACUGCUAAUGUCACCUACUUCCCCCUUCAUUCCCCACAAUGAAUGGAUCCAUUUUCCCCAUGUUCAAGUUCCCAAGAGAGAAUCGACUGCCACUGUAAUUUUUUUUCCUAAUCACUCAUAGGUUACAAGUACCUACCCUGGUCCAGUGAACUGCGGGAUUCAUAUGUGGCCACUUAGGCUGGUCUCGUUGGUAUGGAGCUGUGGGAGGGCAGCACCCAGAAAUAGGCUUUGUUCCAGGCCUGGCACGUACUCCUCCUGCUCCUACUUUCUCUACCUGGGAAAUAGCCGCUCAGGACGAAGCUGCUGCUGUGGUGUCGCCACCUCUGAGAAGUCUCCCAGACCCUCCGACUGCUCUUUAAUUGCCUGUUCUCUCCUCUGGAAGCCUUCCCCCAACACAGAAAAAUUCAAUCCCAUCAUCAAAAAGGGCUUUAGGUUUUCCCUCCAUCUUUACGUGUUGAUCAAAGUUUGCAGAUCUGCUGGAAUCCUUAUUGAAAACUCCCCAUUUCAAACCAACCCGGUCUACAGCCUCCAGGGAAGCUUCCUCCUGGGCUUUGGCUCCAUGUUUUGGUAGAGGGUGGAGGCUUUGGGCAGUGCUCAAACUCCACCGGGAAGUCUCUCUCACUGAGCAGCCCUCCUGCCUGUCAUCCUGGGCAGGCGAGCACUCUGAGGCCCCAGUGUAGCUCUGUGCUUUGAUAUUCCCAAGCUCUGCUGGGGCCUGACUAGGCCAGCCCCAAGGUGGCCAGAGUUCUGGCUUCAUACCUGAGCCAAAAGCCCCAAUCCAUGCUUGGCCAUUGCCUGAGUAUUAGCUGCCCCAGGGGGAUCACGGUCCCCAUAUAUUUGCUUGCCAUGGACCCUGGGCAGCAGGGAGAGAGUAGAGAUUUGUCAAGAGCCCAUGGUGGAGGCUGAGGCCCUGAGGCCAUGAGAUGCAGGCAUGGGGUGAGAAACAGGCCCCUUGGAAUUGGGCUGGGCCUUGGCCCAGCUUAGUCAAAUCAAAAGGCUUCUAUUUGGAGAGCUGAAGAGGGUGUACAGAGGAAGGGGCUAGGUCUGCAAGGAGUGCCUCAUCUCCCUGAAGAGCUCUCAGUGGAACAUACUUCACCCAUCCAUGUACCCACAUCUUUCCUUGCCCAGAAGGCGAGAGCCAGCUAUAACAGACCCAUUUCAAUACCCUGGCAAGUCAUUACUGCCCUUAGCUCUUGGUGUCCCCAUCUGUGAAACAUGGGGGACAGCUGCUAGCCUGGAUUGGAACUUGGGCAAAGUCCAAAGAAUGGGAUUUAGAGCUGAAUGAACCUCACACUGAGGGCACAAUAGCACUAGGCACUGCCCCCAGAGCCUAGUGCUAUAUGCCUGCUGCAGGUCCUACCCAAGCAUGCUUUACUGAGGAACUCAACGUUUCAGAGCUUGAGGGUCAGGUUGAUCAUGGGCUUGUGACCAUAGGCUUCCUUAGUAUGCCAGGCUUGGAGAACCGUGAGAAAAGCAGGGAAGAUACCUUCAAGGGUAGCAGGCAUCAGCUCUACUCACCUUGGCCCAUAAGGCUUUGCCUGGUCAUGCUGGCACCGGGUCAUAUGCUGGACAGGGAGAACGAGAGUCCCAUCCUGGAACUCCAGAAAAGCCCCUGGAUGCUCCAGCCCCUGGGAAAGCACACAGCCAGGCCCUUGGGUGGGAGGUUGGCUUCUAACAGUGCAUACACAUGCCCUUCCUCUGAGUCGGGGCAGCAAAAACAUCCAUUCCGCUGCGCAACAGUUGUCAUUUUUCUAACAUCUGAAAACUCCAGAAGGAGAUGGUGAUAAAUGUGGUACCGGAUUCUGCCUAAAGGAUCAGUCUUUAGAUGUUUUCAGAUUGAAAGCCUCAUUUGUGAUCCUCACAGCCAUCUUGAAAGAAUAGAGCAGCCAGUGGGUAUACUGGAUUGUGAGCUAAGAGGCCUGGGACUUUCCCCCUGUUGCUGCCAGCCAGGUUGAUGACCCUGGGCAAGUCUUUUUCCUUACCAGGUCUCAGUUUCCUCAGCUGUAAAAUGAGAGGUUGAUCUGGAUCAGGGAUAGUAAAUGGGCCUUUGUUCAGUUACUGACUGUUGUAUAACAAACCACCCCCAAAUUUAGUAGCCUUAAUAAACAUUUAUUAGCUCCUGAGUGAGUGGCUUGGCAGUUUGGGCUGUGUUCAGUGUGGUGGUUCUUAUCUCAUCUGGGCCCUCGUGUGGCUGAAGUGAGCUGGCAGAUCAGCUGGGGACUGGCUGGUCUCAGAUGGCCUCGCCCGCCUGUCAGGUGGUUGGCUGGGCAACUGGGCCACACGUUCCAGCAUCUAGCAGGCUGACCCAGGAUUCUAGACAUCAUGGCUGAGUUCCAAAAACCGCAAGAGAAGACAAGCCCAGUAUGCGAGUGCUCUUGAGGAUAUUGCUAUGACGUAUCUUUUGGCCAAAGUAAGUCACAUGGCUAAGCCCAAAUUCUUCUUAACAGGAGGAGCUUCAAAAUAUGGCCAUAUUUAAAAAAUCUACCUCAGGACUCAUUUCACUUGCCAACUCAGAACUUUUAGUAGCAGCUGCCUGGAGUGCCUUUUGAGGAUCUGCAGCAAUUUUCAGACUGUUUGGAAAUACUGACAUGAUAGUUUGGCAGUUUCUCUUAUGAGCAUGGAAUUCAAGUGUGGGCACGUGAGCGUCAGGUAUUUGCCAUCCCUGGCCAGGUUGACCCGUAAGGUCAUAACCUGCCCCAUAGGAUGUUAUAUGCAGUAGGCCUGUCUGACAAGACCACAGAAAUAGAGAAGGCAAAGCAGAGCAAAAGAUUCUGAGCCAGGCAUCCUUGGUUUUCAUCCCAACCAGAUCAUUGAUUGAUUGAGGUUUUAGGCAAAUCAAAAUCCCUCCACCAGUAGCCAGAUUCUUCAUAAUAAACUUCCUCCAUAACAGUAAACCAUUUCCUGAACACCUGCUGUUAAAAAGCACAUUUUACAUUUACUUAAUCUCCACAACCACCCUCAGUAGGUGUAGUAAGGACUUCUGGUUACAAGUUACAGAAACUGAAUUCAGUCCUGCUUAGUGGGAGGAAGUUUAUUGGCUCACAAAUUGUAAAGUCCAGGGAUCUUCAGACAUGGGGACUUGGGUUCAAAAGCUGCCAUCGAGAAUCCGGUUAGCCAGGCAUGGUGACACGUGCCUGUAGUCCCCGCUACUUGGGGGACUACAGUGGGAGAUCAUUUGCACCUAGGAGGUUAAUGCUGCGGUGAGCCAUGAUCCUGCCGCUGCACUCCAGCCUGGGUGACAAAGCGAGACCCCAACUCAAGGGGAAAAAAUCUGGUUUUCGGGCAGGUUCCAAGAAGUGGUAGAGCAUGGCCAUAGGGCCUGUGAGAAUAGAGGGACAGAGGGGAGAAUCCCCAAAAGGAGAGCAAGGCUUGGCUAACAAAAACAGGCAUCCACUGUGUGGUUAUGUCUAUUCUAUAGAUUUUGUAGAUGAGGUUUAAAAGCAUGGCCCCAAGUAAAGGUGGCAUCUCUAUCCUAUCCUCGCCUUUAUCUAAACUCUGUGACCGAUCAAUAGCAUAUGAUGGUGGUGGUGCUCUGCCAGUCUCCCAGUCCCAGACUGAAGCACUAGCAGCUUCCACUUAUUAUCUCUUGGGACUCUAGCUCUUGGGACCCAACCACCAUGCUGUGAAGCAGCCCAGGCCACACAGAGAGGCCACGUGUACAUGUUCAGCUGACAGCAGUAUCAAAUGUCAGACAUGAGAGAGGAAGGCUUCAAGAUGACUCCAGCCCAGCCACCGUCUGAGAACAAAGUAAGAACUGCCUCACUGAUGCCAUUCAAAGCCCAGCACCAUGAGAGAUAAUAAAACGUUGUUUGAAGAUGCUAA